UGUCCCACCCCUCCCUAGACCCCUCAACAUUCAGGCUGGUAAAAUGAGGCUGCAGUGAAGAGUCCUGGGCUCUGAGGAUGGGAGGCUCAUUGUUGCUGGGAGCAGAAAAGCUGGCCCACUGUUGACACAUGGUCUCCAGCUCCUCUUCCACCCUCAAAGUUUAAUUCCUCUGAACCUGCUCCUUCCCCACCCUUCUAGGAGAGCAACCCUGAAUUGAUCACUGCCAUUUUGACAUUCUUCUUUUCUUUAUUUUUCUAAUGUGAGAUUCUGAAACCUCUUCUUACCACCCCACACAAUUGGGUUAGCCCCAGAUCCUGCCUUAGGGCACAAAGAUUUGCCUCUCAGAAUUCCUUCCUUGCCUUUUUUAAAGGCCUGACCAGGGUCUUUGUGGUUGGAAUGGGGGUGUGUUAGGAGUGGCGAUGGGAGGCUGGAGUGCGAAAGCUACAAGCAAGGGCAAUAAACUGGGGGCCCACUGGGGCAGAUGUCUUAAUGGAGAGAGCAGAGAUGAAGAGAAAAUCCCUCAGCAGGUUGAGAGUGACUUCUGCAGGCUCAGGGCACAAAGCGAGAUCUCUUUGCACAGAAUUUCGAUCAUCCUUGCUACUUAAGACCCCCAAAAUGGUGGAACCCAGGGGUACAGAGAGCUAAGGAAGGAAAACUCCAUACUUGAGAUGCCUUCUUGAGCCAGCAGUGGCAGUAGUGGUGGUGGAGGCAACAGUUAGAUGAACUGACUGGUCCUGACCACACAGUGUCAAAAUAGAGAAUGGAGAGCAGGUCUGCUGUUUACCAAAGAAGACCGAAACAUGGCCCACGUGUCCAAUCCUUGCUUGGAGGAGGAGCCGGGAGGAUACCCUUGAUGAACUGCUCUCAGAUUGUUGGUCUAUGAAGGAGGUUAAUACAUGUCAGUUUGACAUUGUAUCAUUGAAUCAGAAUUGAACAUCAGAAAGAGUAAAAUUCCCAGGCCUUUUUUACCCUAGCCUGGGUACAAGCUCAAGAUGAUGCAGAAGGAGGAGCAAAGCAUGGGAUCCAAGAAAGUUAAGUUCCAGCUCAGGUCGAAGAGAAUCAUGUCUGUGAUCUGUGUCUUUGGUUUCUUCAUCUACAGCUGUCAUCUUGUGGGCUGGAGCAUGGUGGCCAGGAAGUGUGCAAGGGGCUCUGGUGUCCAUGCAGCCCUCAUAGACCUGAGGAGACUACUCUUUUGAGCUUCUGACCACCCAUCAGCAUUGGAUUAGAGAUUCUGGACUAAAUGACUUUCUCCAGGAAUAGUUGCUGGUGGACAAAACUUCCAGAUUCUCUGAGACUGAGGAGAGAUGUCUUACCAGCAGCAGCAGUGCAAGCAGCCCUGCCAGCCACCUCCUGUGUGCCCCACGCCAAAGUGCCCAGAGCCAUGUCCACCCCCGAAGUGCCCUGAGCCUUACCUGCCUCCUCCUUGUCCACCUGAGCAUUGCCCACCUCCACCAUGCCAGGAUAAAUGCCCUCCUGUGCAACCAUACCCACCCUGCCAGCAGAAGUAUCCACCCAAGAGCAAGUAACAUCACUAGAAUUCAUCAGGACCAUGAAACAACAAGAUCCAGUGGCUCUUCUUACUCCCAGGACUCCAUCAUCUUCCCUUCAGCUGUAGUGGGAGGCUGCAUCUUCCCUAACCUCUGUCUGGCUUGAGCGUUGACAGAGAAAAGGCUUAGUUCUGAAAACCGAUAUGUUGUUGGAAGAUGAGCAGCCAGAUCACUGCCUAAUCUCGCUUUGCUGUCUGUGAUGUAGAUGGUGGUUCCUAUCCUGAGAGCAAGUGUGUUUAUUCUUUUGCUUCUCCCCAAUAAAGCACAUGUUUCAUGGUCAAGCCCA